GAGUACUGUGAAGAUGUGGUCCCCAAGGCUAGAGCUGAAAAGAGGCUUAGGGCCGGGUGAGCCUUCCAGCCAGGGCCUGCCUCCAAGUGAUGCUCCCCCAGGGCAGGGGGCAUAAGGAUGGCACCCAGCCAGGUGGGAGCCUGGGCCCUGCCCAGCCUCAAAGCUUUGAGCUCAGGAAAUCCGGAGGCAGGGGAGGGGGACAUCGUUGCCACAUUCCCCAGCCCUUUAAGACCCCCAAGGCAGGAAGGCUGCCCGGGCCUCACCAGCUUCCCUCACAGGCUCCUUCCUGGGAGGAAGGGGCUGCCUGUGCCCUCGAAGGCGCAAGGGAGGGCAGGAGGGAGGCUCGGAAGGUGUUGCAAUCCCCAGCCCCCGGGCCUGUCAGAGGCUGAGCCAUUAACGACAGAGCUCGGGGAGAGAAGCUGGACUGCAGCUGGUUUCAGGAACUUCUCUUGACGAGAAGAGAGACCAAGGAGGCCAAGCAGGGGCUGGGCCAGAGGUGCCAACAUGGGGAAACUGAGGCUCGGCUCGGAAAGGUGAAGUAACUUGUCCAAGAUCACAAAGCUGGGAUAAAUUGACCCUCCAGUGGACAGCUCUGAGAAGUGUUCUACAUGGCUCUUUGGAAGGUUCCAGCAGGAUAGAGCCCCAGUUGUCCAUAGAGGUGAACAUCAAGUUGGUGCUAUGGCAAGGCUGGGAAACUGCAGCCUGACUUGGGCUGCCCUGAUCAUCCUGCUGCUCCCCGGAAGUCUGGAGGAGUGCGGGCACAUCAGUGUCUCAGCCCCCAUCGUCCACCUGGGGGAUCCCAUCACAGCCUCCUGCAUCAUCAAGCAGAACUGCAGCCAUCUGGACCCGGAGCCACAGAUUCUGUGGAGACUGGGAGCAGAGCUUCAGCCCGGGGGCAGGCAGCAGCGUCUGUCUGAUGGGACCCAGGAAUCUAUCAUCACCCUGCCCCACCUCAACCACACUCAGGCCUUUCUCUCCUGCUGCCUGAACUGGGGCAACAGCCUGCAGAUCCUGGACCAGGUUGAGCUGCGCGCAGGCUACCCUCCAGCCAUACCCCACAACCUCUCCUGCCUCAUGAACCUCACAACCAGCAGCCUCAUCUGCCAGUGGGAGCCAGGACCUGAGACCCACCUACCCACCAGCUUCACUCUGAAGAGUUUCAAGAGCCGGGGCAACUGUCAGACCCAAGGGGACUCCAUCCUGGACUGCGUGCCCAAGGACGGGCAGAGCCACUGCUGCAUCCCACGCAAACACCUGCUGUUGUACCAGAAUAUGGGCAUCUGGGUGCAGGCAGAGAAUGCGCUGGGGACCAGCAUGUCCCCACAACUGUGUCUUGAUCCCAUGGAUGUUGUGAAACUGGAGCCCCCCAUGCUGCGGACCAUGGACCCCAGCCCUGAAGCGGCCCCUCCCCAGGCAGGCUGCCUACAGCUGUGCUGGGAGCCAUGGCAGCCAGGCCUGCACAUAAAUCAGAAGUGUGAGCUGCGCCACAAGCCGCAGCGUGGAGAAGCCAGCUGGGCACUGGUGGGCCCCCUCCCCUUGGAGGCCCUUCAGUAUGAGCUCUGCGGGCUCCUCCCAGCCACGGCCUACACCCUGCAGAUACGCUGCAUCCGCUGGCCCCUGCCUGGCCACUGGAGCGACUGGAGCCCCAGCCUGGAGCUGAGAACUACCGAACGGGCCCCCACUGUCAGACUGGACACAUGGUGGCGGCAGAGGCAGCUGGACCCCAGGACAGUGCAGCUGUUCUGGAAGCCAGUGCCCCUGGAGGAAGACAGCGGACGGAUCCAAGGUUAUGUGGUUUCUUGGAGACCCUCAGGCCAGGCUGGGGCCAUCCUGCCCCUCUGCAACACCACAGAGCUCAGCUGCACCUUCCACCUGCCUUCAGAAGCCCAGGAGGUGGCCCUUGUGGCCUAUAACUCAGCCGGGACCUCUCGUCCCACUCCGGUGGUCUUCUCAGAAAGCAGAGGCCCAGCUCUGACCAGACUCCAUGCCAUGGCCCGAGACCCUCACAGCCUCUGGGUAGGCUGGGAGCCCCCCAAUCCAUGGCCUCAGGGCUAUGUGAUUGAGUGGGGCCUGGGCCCCCCCAGCGCGAGCAAUAGCAACAAGACCUGGAGGAUGGAACAGAAUGGGAGAGCCACGGGGUUUCUGCUGAAGGAGAACAUCAGGCCCUUUCAGCUCUAUGAGAUCAUCGUGACUCCCUUGUACCAGGACACCAUGGGACCCUCCCAGCAUGUCUAUGCCUACUCUCAAGAAAUGGCUCCCUCCCAUGCCCCAGAGCUGCAUCUAAAGCACAUUGGCAAGACCUGGGCACAGCUGGAGUGGGUGCCUGAGCCCCCUGAGCUGGGGAAGAGCCCCCUUACCCACUACACCAUCUUCUGGACCAACGCUCAGAACCAGUCCUUCUCCGCCAUCCUGAAUGCCUCCUCCCGUGGCUUUGUCCUCCAUGGCCUGGAGCCCGCCAGUCUGUAUCACAUCCACCUCAUGGCUGCCAGCCAGGCUGGGGCCACCAACAGUACAGUCCUCACCCUGAUGACCUUGACCCCAGAGGGGUCGGAGCUACACAUCAUCCUGGGCCUGUUCGGCCUCCUGCUGUUGCUCACCUGCCUCUGUGGAACUGCCUGGCUCUGUUGCAGCCCCAACAGGAAGAAUCCCCUCUGGCCAAGUGUCCCAGACCCAGCUCACAGCAGCCUGGGCUCCUGGGUGCCCACAAUCAUGGAGGAGCUGCCCGGACCCAGACAGGGACAGUGGCUGGGGCAGACAUCUGAAAUGAGCCGUGCUCUCACCCCACAUCCUUGUGUGCAGGAUGCCUUCCAGCUGCCCGGCCUUGGCACGCCACCCAUCACCAAGCUCACAGUGCUGGAGGAGGAUGAAAAGAAGCCGGUGCCCUGGGAGUCCCAUAACAGCUCAGAGACCUGUGGCCUCCCCACUCUGGUCCAGACCUAUGUGCUCCAGGGGGACCCAAGAGCAGUUUCCACCCAGCCCCAAUCCCAGUCUGGCACCAGCGAUCAGGUCCUUUAUGGGCAGCUGCUGGGCAGCCCCACAAGCCCAGGGCCAGGGCACUAUCUCCGCUGUGACUCCACUCAGCCCCUCUUGGCGGGCCUCACCCCCAGCCCCAAGUCCUAUGAGAACCUCUGGUUCCAGGCCAGCCCCUUGGGGACCCUGGUAACCCCAGCCCCAAGCCAGGAGGACGACUGUGUCUUUGGGCCACUGCUCAACUUCCCCCUCCUGCAGGGGAUCCGGGUCCAUGGGAUGGAGGCGCUGGGGAGCUUCUAGGGCUUCCUGGGGUUCCCUUCUUGGGCCUGCCUCUUAAAGGCCUGAGCUAGCUGGAGAAGAGGGGAGGGUCCAUAAGCCCAUGACUAAAAACUACCCCAGCCCAGGCUCUCACCAUCUCCAGUCACCAGCAUCUCCCUCUCCUCCCAAUCUCCAUAGGCUGGGCCUCCCAGGCGAUCUGCAUACUUUAAGGACCAGAUCAUGCUCCAUCCAGCCCCACCCAAUGGCCUUUUGUGCUUGUUUCCUAUAACUUCAGUAUUGUAAACUAGUUUUUGGUUUGCAGUUUUUGUUGUUGUUUAUAGACACUCUUGGGUGUA